CUGUCUUACAGCUGAUCCGGUUCUUGCGGCGGUGCGUGCUGGCGCCGGAGAGUUCCGCGCGUGUCCUCGGGCUGUCCGCGGGGAAGCUGGUCCGGGAGUGGGCGCCCGCCCGCCUGCCUCGCGCCUUGCGCCCCCGGCACCGCUUCCAGAAGGGAAAGUCGCCGCCGCUCGCGGUAGACCCGGGCAGCGCUUCCAUUCCGCGGAGCUGGAAAUAGGGAUCCAGCCAUCCGUGGGUCAGGAGGAAUGGAGACUGUACCUUCCACAUAGAUUCACAAGCUGCCCUGCAGUGGCCUUGGCUUCAGGAAAGGAGCAUUCAGACGCUUCCGUCAGCCUCCCAGGAUGGCAGCCCCUGACCUGGCCCACGGAGGUCAUGUUUCUAGGGACUCAGUCUGCCUUCAUGAAGAACAGACACAGGCAGCAGGGAUGGUGGCUGGCUGGCUGAUAAAUUGUUACCAGGACGCGGUGACCUUUGACGACGUGGCUGUGGACUUCACCCAGGAGGAAUGGACUUUACUGGACCCAUCUCAGAGAGACCUCUACAGAGAUGUGAUGCUGGAAAACUACGAGAACCUGGCCUCAGUAGGACAUCACCUGUUCCAACCCAGUGUGAUCUAUUGGCUGGAGCAGGAAGAGGAGUUGAGGGCAGGGCGGAGAGCAGUUCUCCAAGAAUGGCGACUUAAAACCAAAGGGCCAGCACUUCGGCAGGAUAGAUCUUGGUUCAGAGCAUCAAAUGAGACACAGACGGCAAGAAGCCACAAUGGAGGGCAGCUCUGUGACCGCACGCAGUGUGGAGAAGCUUUCAGUGAACACUCAGGCCUCAGCACACACGUGAGAACUCAAAAUACAGGAGACAGUUGUGUGUCUAAUCAUUAUGAAAGGGACUUUUUUAUUCCAUGCCAGAAAACCUUGUUCAAAAUUGGAGAGCAGUUUUCCGUGUUGGGUCAGUGUGGAAAAGCCUUCAGCUCUACUCCAAAUGUUGUUUCCCAGCAAGCAUGCACUCGGGACAGAUCUCUUGACUACAGCAGCUGUGGGGAAGUGUUCCUUAAUCAGUCAUACCUUCAGGCACGUGCGGGAAGUCACAACGGAGAAGAAACAUGGAAAUGGAAGCCGUGUGGGAAAGCUCUAACUCACUCCAUGGGCUGCGCCACACCUGUUGAAAUGCAUGCCGUCAGGAAUCCCCACGUAUGUAGGGAAUGUGGGAAGGCCUUUAGGUACACUGCCUACCUUACUGGUCGCGUGCAAGUCCACCCUGGGGAAAAGCCCUGUGAAUUGGAAGAAUGUGGAAAAGCCUCCCCUGUUUCUUCCAGCCUAACUCAACAUGUAAGAAUUCAUGCUGCAGAGAAACCCUGUGAAUGUAAAGAAUGCGGAAAAGCCUUCACUGGACUCUCAGGUCUUUCUAAACACGUCCAAACAGACCCUGGACAGAAGCCCUAUGAAUGUAAGGACUGUGGGAAAGCCUGCGGUGGGUUUUAUCUACUGAAUGAGCAUGGAAAAACUCACACGAGGGAGAAGCCCUUUGCAUGUGUGGUUUGCGGAAAAUAUUUUAGAAAUUCCUCAUGCCUUAAUAAUCAUGUUCGAAUUCACACUGGAAUAAAACCCUAUACAUGCAGCUACUGUGGGAAGGCCUUCACUGUGCGCUGUGGCCUUACUAGACACGUACGAACACACACGGGCGAGAAGCCAUACACGUGUAAGGACUGCGGGAAAGCCUUCUGUACAUCCUCGGGCCUUACUGAGCAUGUAAGGACUCACACUGGAGAGAAACCAUAUGAAUGUAAAGAUUGUGGGAAAUCCUUCACUGUUUCUUCAAGCCUGACUGAGCACGCGAGAAUCCAUACCGGAGAGAAACCCUACGAAUGUAAGCAGUGUGGCAAAGCCUUCACAGGGCGCUCAGGCCUCACUAAACACAUGCGGACACACACCGGGGAGAAGCCCUAUGAAUGUAAGGACUGUGGGAAAGCCUACAAUAGGGUUUAUCUACUGAAUGAGCAUGUGAAAACUCACACAGAGGAGAAGCCCUUUAUAUGUACGGUAUGCAGGAAAUCCUUCAGAAAUUCCUCGUGCCUGAAUAAGCACAUUCAGAUUCACACUGGAAUAAAACCUUAUGAAUGUAAGGACUGUGGGAAAACAUUCACUGUUUCUUCGAGCCUAACCGAGCACAUACGAACUCACACUGGAGAGAAACCUUAUGAAUGUAAAGUAUGCGGAAAGGCCUUCACCACAUCCUCACACCUUAUCGUGCACAUAAGAACCCACACCGGUGAGAAACCCUACAUAUGUAAGGAGUGUGGGAAAGCCUUUGCUUCCUCCUCACACCUUAUCGAACACAGAAGGACUCACACAGGAGAGAAACCUUACAUAUGUAACGAGUGUGGGAAAGCCUUCCGUGCCUCCUCUCACCUGCAUAAACAUGGAAGAAUUCACACUGGGCAGAAACCCUAUAAAUGUAAGGAAUGUGGGAAAGCAUACAAUAGGUUUUAUCUACUAAAAGAACAUUUAAAAACUUACACUGAAGAGCAGGUUUUUGUAUGUAAGGACUGUGGAAAAUCUUUUAAGAAUUCCUCAUGCCUUAACCAUCACACUCAAAUUCACACUGAUGAGAAACCUUUCUAAUGUAAAGAAUGUGGGGAAGCUGUCAGCUACACUCAUUCACGUUGAAGACAUGAAAGACCUCUCGUUCUCCAGAUGUCCAUGACUUGAGGAAUGUGGCUAGGCAAUCAGCAUCUCAUCACAACCCGGCAGGCAGGAACUCACCCUGGAGCCCUAUGCAGCAGACACAGAGAAAGCCCUCAGUGUUCUCUAAGGUCUUGCUGAAUAUGGAUGGUAUCCAGUAGAGAGAACUCUAUUGAUGUGUGAUAUGCAGCAGCAUUGUUGCUGUUCUGCUCAGUACUUUGAUGAUCCCUUGUGAUCUCACAAUGAAGAAAAACCUUAGGAGGGUGAGAAUUGUUGGGAAGUCAUUUUUUACAUUACAUCUUUCCUCACCCUUUAGUAAACGUGGUGAUUGACACUUGAAGUGUUGUGAAUGUAUGGAAGAUAGCAGUCGCUUCCCUGUGUUCUAAAACCUUGUGGGCUAACUUGAGACAUGUCUUUCUGGGGGUUCUGUAGACGUAUUUUGAAUCUUUAUGAUGCUGCACUGAUCAUUCUUGGAGUGAGGACUCUGUUCCCUGUAGAAAUCCUCCAGUCUGGUUGCUACAGUGUCCACGUCGCAGCCUGGCUAACAGUAGGCCUUGAGGACUCAGAUGUGAUCCUGUGUGAGCAGUGUAGGCUCUGGUUGGUUAGUCUUGAGGAUCCAGAUGUGAUUCUUUGAGCAGCGUAGGCUCUGGUUGGUUAGUCUUGAGGAUCCAGAUGUGAUUCUGUGAGCAGUGUAAGCUCUGGUUGGUUAGUCUUCAGGAUCCAGAUGUGAUCUUGUGUGAGCACUGUAGGCUCUGGUUGGUUAGUCUUGAGGAUCCAGAUGUGAUUCUGUGAGCAGUGUAGGCUCUGGUUGGUUAGUCUUGAGGAUGCAGAUGUGAUUCUGUGUGAGCAGCGUAGGCUCUGGUUGGUUAGUCUUGAGGAUCCAGAUGUGAUUCUGUGAGCAGCAUAGGCUCUGGUUGGUUAGUCUUGAGGAUCCAGAUGUGAUUCUGUGAGCAGCGUAGGCUCUGGUUGGUUAGUCUUGAGGAUCCAGAUGUGAUUCUGUGAGCAGCGUAGGCUCUGCUUGGUUAGUCUUGAGGAUCCAGAUGUGAUCCUGCGUGAGCAGCGUAGGCUCUGGUUGGUUAGUCUUGAGGAUCCAGAUGUGAUCCUGUGUGAGCAGCGUAGGCUCUGGUUGGUUAGUCUUGAGGAUCCAGAUGUGAUUCUGUGAGCAGUGUAGGCUCUGGUUGGUUAGUCUUAGGUAUCCAGAUGUGAUCCUGUGUGAGCAGCGUAGGCUCUGGUUGGUUAGUCUUGAGGAUCCAGAUGUGAUCCUGUGUGAGCAGCGUAGGCUCUGGUUGGUUAGUGUUGAGGAUCCAGAUGUGAUUCUGUGAGCAGUGUAGGCUCUGGUUGGUUAGUCUUGAGGAUCCAGAUGUGAUCCUGUGUGAGCAGUGUAGGCUCUGGUUGGUUAGUCUUAAGUAUCCAGAUGGGAUCCUGUAUGAGCAGCGUAGGCUCUGGUUGGUUAGUCAUGCUCUUAGGCAUGACCCACCUGUAGGGUCCCACACUGGCCAAUGUUGGGGCAUAACACAGCUCUACAUUUUAUGAAAAUGCCCUUGUUCCUCUCCCAUACCUGAUCCCUUCAGAUAAAACACCAGGGUGCAAGGAGGGGCAGAGUGGAGAGGGGCGAGGUCUGUACCCUGAGAUGCCCCCGUUUCAUGGCCGUGGAGGGAGAACCACCACCCCCCACGUGGGGAGGAGGGAAUUCCUGUACCUUAGGCAGUGCCGGACGGGUGAGAGCCCUGAGUGUCCUUGUUGACCUCCAGAUCCUCUUCACAGCAUGCAGAGCGGUCCUGGCAGCUGCUGCAAUCUGGCACUCCUGGGGCAGCUGCUGCGAUCCGGCACUGAUGAGGCAGCUGCUGUGAUCCGGCAUUCAUGGGGCAGCUGCUGCGACCCGGCACUCCUGGGGCAGCUGCUGCUUGUGUGUGUGCUGCUCCUUUGUGUACCAUGAAAACAGACCAGGGACACGGCUGGUCCUGAUGUUCUGUGGCGCUUGGCCCUGUCACUGGCGCUUCUUGGAUGAGGCCCUUAAACACACACAGUGGCAGAGCAAGACUUCAUGUGAGUGACACGAAUGUGUGUCCUCUGGCUGCAGCAAUCCUGGGUUAUGUUUUUUGUGGCCAUCAGGGCAGCAGCUGCUUGGUGACUGUUUCUGUGGUGUUGAAUCCCCACGGUAUAAAGGUAAUCUACAACGAGGUGAACAAUAAAUCCUGGAUGGACAGACCCGUGCACCUUCAUAUUACGUGUUUGAAAUCCUGGAUGGACAGACCCGUCCACCUUCAUGUCACGUGUUUGAAAUUCUGGAUGGACAGACCCAUGCACCUUCAUGUUACGUGUUUAAAAUUCUGGAUGGACAGACCCGUGCACCUUCCUGUCACAUGUUUGAAAUCCUGGAUGGACAGACCUGUGCACCUUCAUGUCACGUGUUUGAAAUUCUGGAUGGACAGAGCCAUGCACCUUCAUGUUACGUGUUUGUUGUGGAGAGGAGUGGGUUGUGCCAUGUUUCUCUUGUGGGAUUGAGUGUGGCUAUUUAGCUCAUCUGUUGCCACCUUUAAUUGUUGGCAUUGACACUAAAGGUCAUCAGAUUAGCGGGAACCAGCUUGUGGGGUUGUAGCGGCUCCUGGACUGGUCUCAGGUGACAUCCUGAUUGGCUGAAAUAAGUCCUGCAGGUCUCUGCUAGAACUGACUCACAGUUGCCUGAGUCCAGAACUUGUGGGUCACAGGUGACGCCAGGACUGCAUCAUCCUGGUGCUCGGACUCCUAGUGACAGCAUCCUGAGCAGGCGGUAGCCCAGACACCACCCUGCCUGAUAUGCCCACUGUUGGUGGAGACAUCACCCCAGCACAGACCUCAAUUAAGACGACUACCCCUCCGACGACUCCCCCUCCCUUCACUGGAGGUGACUUCACGCACUUCUUCAGAACCUCCUCAGCAGCGAUGCCCAUGGACUGGGGUUCCUAAGGCACAAAUUUGAUAUUUGAGAUUCUGUGAUGAGCUGAGCUUGCUGUCCGCUAACCCGUGAUCCUGGUGUAAUCUCAACCAAAACCCACAGCCCUGCACCCCUUGCCUGUAGGAAAAUCUGGUAGGAGUUAGUAGUGUCUGUGAAGUCUCAAUAAUUGAUACCAAAAUGUUUUGUUUCACCAGGAGGUGCCCGCCUCCUAUCAGCCUCUGGGAAGGCCACUGUCUCCCCAGUGCCUUCUCCUCCGCUGCAGCUUUCCAUCUCAUCUCCUUACUCCCUUGACUUGGCUUCACACAGAGCCUCUUCUUUACACAUACUAACUGUUUGCUUCAUACCCUCCUGCAGCAGAACUACAGACCUGCCAUCCUGAUAAUUGUCAAACUCAUCCCUUUAUCACCUUUAUAACUCCUCAAGGAUAUUAUCAUUGGACCCCCAACAUUUCAAAGUGAUUUUCUUGAGUAAUACCAUAUGCUGUGAUGUGGAUGUGAUUGGUUUGCCCUCAUCAAGUCUCAUGUUGAGCUUUGACCCUCAGUGUGGCAGUGCUGGGAGGGGGCCUGGUGGGGGUUUGGGUCAUGGGGGCACCCUCCUGAAUGGUUGGAUACCAUUCAUUCUUGCUGUGUCAAGCCUGGAUUGGUUUGUAGGGGAAUGCACUAGUUACUGGGAGCAUGGUUGUGAUAAAGCCAAGCCGUCCCUCGGGUUUGGCUCACUGCCCUUGACCUUCUCUGCCCUGUUUGACACAGCAAAUAGUCCUCACCAGAAGCAGGUCAGAUGCCAGUGCUAUGCUUGCACAGCCUGCUGAACCAUGAGCCAAAUAAGCCUCUUUCUAAGUUACCCACAGCCUCAGAUAUGUAGCAACACAGACAGACUAAGACACCAAGCAUGAUGGAAAACUGGGUUAUGGGCAGGACUGCAAGUACUGGUUAGGCAGAUACCUGUAUUUCUCUUCCUAACUCUCAGAACGUGUUCUGUGUCACUUAGGGCAACUUAUGCCCUCCUGUGUGAAAAUCUCCACUCCCAAUGUCUGAGGGUUCCUCAGAGUAAGAUAAAAUAUUAAAGGACCAAUUGUAUUAAUUAUGUUUUUUUUUUUUUUGUUAGGGUACAUUUUCAUCCUGGGGUCUUGCUGUGGGGGCUAGACCGUCCCUCUCAGGCUAGAUCAUUCCUAAAGAUGGUAAACAACUUGCUGGAAACAUGCACUGCAUAUACAAAUCAACUCACUGCAUAUGCACAUCAACUCACUGCAUAUGCAACUCAACUCACACCGUAUAUGCAACUCAACUCACACCGUGUAUGCAAAUCAACUCGCACUGCGUAUGCAACUCAACUCGCACUGCGUAUGCAACUCAACUCGCACUGCGUAUGCGAAUCCACUCACUGCCUAUGCAACUCAGCUCGCUCUGCGUAUGCAACUGAGCUCGCUCUGCGUAUGCAACCCAGCUCGCUCUGCGUAUGCAACUCAAGUCGCACUGCGUAUGCAACUCAGCUCGCUCUGCGUAUGCAACUCAGCUCGCACUGCGUAUGCAACUCAGCUCGCACUGCGUAUGCAAGUCAGCUCGCUCUGCGUAUGCAACUCAGCUCGCUCUGCGUAUGCAACUCAGCUCGCACUGCGUAUGCAACUCAGCUCGCACUGCGUAUGCAACUCAGCUCGCUCUGCGUAUGCAACUCAGCUCGCUCUGCGUAUGCAACUCAGCUCGCUCUGCGUAUGCAACUCAGCUCGCACUGCGUAUGCAACUCAGCUCGCUCUGCGUAUGCAACUCAGCUCGCUCUGCGUAUGCAACUCAGCUCGCACUGCGUAUGCAACUCGCACUGCGUAUGCAACUCAACUCGCACUGCGUAUGCAACUCAACUCGCACUGCGUAUGCAACUCAACUCGCACUGCGUGUGCAACUCAACUCGCACUGCGUGUGCAACUCAACUCACACUGCGUAUGCAACUCAGCUUGCUCUGUGUAUGCAACUCAACUCGCACUGCGUAUGCAAAUCAACUCACUGCAUAUGCAACUCAGCUCGCACUGCAUAUGCAACGCAACUCAACUCAUACUGCAUAUGCAACUCAACUCACACUGUAUGCAACUCAGCUCGCUCUGCAUAUGCAAUUCAACUCGCACUGCGUAUGCAAAUCAACUUACUGCAUAUGCAACUCAACUCACUGCGUAUGCAACUCAACUCGCACUGCAUAUGCAACUCAACUCGCACUGCGUAUGCAACUCAACUCGCACUGCGUAUGCAACUCAGCUCGCACUGCGUAUGCAACUCAACUGUUGCAAGUACUUAUUUCCGGCCACUUCCUUUUUCUAACUACCACACCAAGCCAGUAUUUCUCCUCCCUGAAGUCAGCCCAGGAUGAGGCACUAGACAGCAGGACAUGCUGUAUGCCCUUGGGCCUGCUGGAAGUAUGCAGACUAGCCAGCCCCAGACUUCAUCCUGCCCUGUCCUGCCUUUCCUGUGAAAACCCUGUGGCCUCUGCCUCCCCUGGCUCUGACUUCUGCCUCCUGCCCAGCUCUGCAGCUCCCCUUGGGCCCUGCCUGGAGUGAUGUGCCGCCUUCUCUUGACACUGUGAGUGAUAAACUUUCCAUGUCAGGAACCUGUGUGUGUCACUCACUCACCUUGACGAGUCCGCGUCUAGGCCCCACCAGUGGUGUGGUUUUCCUCAUAGUCUCUCUACCUAAGCACAUGUCUGUGACAAGGUCUUACCCAGCCCAGGGAUUCUUGAACUAUCUGUAGGAACUGCCAUGUUGACUCCUGGGCAGUUUUAUUCUUUCUCUCUACUCGUUCAACCUUCUUAGGGAGUGACGUUUUUUCCAAAGUGGUUGUGAAACAGCAUCUCCUUGGGGUGUUGGUUUGCACUUCUCUUCAUUACUGAUAGUAUGAACAUGGUUUUGCUUACGCUGGCUAUUUUCCUUUUUGGAUGAAGUACCUGGUCUUGUUUUUUCCUGGUUUGUUUGAUCUUUGUUCUUUUUUAGAAAUAGUGAGGCUGUUGUGAGGUGAGUCACCACUUGUGACUUAGAAGAUUGCAGUGGUUUCCACUUCACCUGUUUCCACUUUUGUGAUGAUGCCUUAAGGAAAAAGAUUGUGCCAGGUGUGGUGGCUCAGGCCUGUAAUCCCAACACUUUGGGAGGCCGAGGUGGGUGGAUCACAAGGUCAGGAGAUCAAGACCAUCCUGGCCAACAUGGUGAAACGCCAUCUCUACUAAAAAUAGAAAAAUUGGCUAGAUGUGGUGGUGCACGCCUGUAAUCCCAGCUCCUUGGGAGGCUGAGGCAGGAGAAUUGCUUGAAGAUGGGAAGCACAGAUUGCAGUGAACCGAGAUCGCGCCACUGCACUCCAGCCUGGCAACAGAGUGAGACUCUGUCUCAAAAAAAAAGGAAAAAUAUUUCUUAAUUUUGGCAUACUCAAAUUUAUACAACCUUUCCUUUAUCUUCAUCAGAAAUUUCUUUUCUCCUAAGGCCUUAAAUAUGCUGUACUAUUUUGGCUUCCACAGUUUCUAUGUUUUAUCCCAAGUUGCUUAAUCCAUUUGGAGUUGAUUUUUGUUGACCGUAUCUGUAGAGUGUAAUGUCAUUUUUCCCACUAUGGACAUAAAAAUUUUUGCAAGGCCUCUUUUUUUUAAUGAAGAAAAGAGGUUUAUUUUGUUCACAAUUCUGAAGGCCUGGAGGGUCCCAGAAGCUUGGCACCAGCACCCACUAGGCUCCAGAUCGGGGCCUCAUGCUGACUUCCGUUUUCACACAACGAGUGGGAAACAGGUGUCCUAACACUGUGAGAGAAAAAAUCCGAAAGUUUAGUUUUUCCCAUUCGCUUGCCCUGGCCUCCAGGCAGUCCUGCAGCAGCAAACACAUCAUCAGCCUUAGGAGCUGGCCUGUGAGGUUGACCACUCUGUAGGUGGACGAGCCUCGCCCGAGAAGAGACAUGAGCAGUUCUGCGUAGGCUUUAAGACAGAAUCAACAUGGAAAGCACGACCCACAUGGUUUCAAUAGAACUUGCCUCCUGAACCUGACUAGGUUACUCGCCUGAUGAACCAGUAUCUCCAUCACCCGUGGGACUGACAGACCCAGAGUGUCAUAACCUAAAAUUCAGAAGUGUAGACUAUAAUCUUAAAUUAUUCAGCAUAUGUGCAACAGCCUUGGGGAGCAGUGUUAUGAUACCAAAUGGCUAACAUUCAUGACCUCAGUAUCCUGGAAGAAAAGGAGAAAGUGUGAUGUAGUAAAACCACUUGAAAAAAUAAUGAUGAAACAUUUCUCAUAUUUGGUGUAAGAUAAAAACUUAAGUUUGAAGAGGUUCCAUGAGCCCCAGACAGGAUAAACCUAAAGAAAACCAAGCCCAGGCCGGGGGCGGUGGCUCACACCUGUAAUCCCAGCACUUUGGGAGGCCGAGGUGGGCGGAUCACAAGGUCAGGAGAUCAUGACCAUCCUGGCCAACACAGUGAAACCUCGUCUCUAGUAAAAAAAAAAAAAAAAAAGAAAAAUACAAAAAUUUAGUUGGGCGUGGUGGCGGGCGACUGCAGUCCCAGCUACUGGGGAGGCUGAGGCAGGAGAAUGGCGUGAACCCGGGAGGCAGAGCAUGCAGUGAGCUGAGAUUGCACCACUGCACUCCAGCCUGGGCAACAGAGCGAGACUCUGUCUCAAAAAAGAAGAAAGAAAAGAAAACCAAGCCCCUGCCACCACGAAGCUGCCGAAAGCUACAGAGUGAAAGUCUUGGAAGGAGGCUGAGAAAGUGGACACAGUGCUUCCAGAAGAACAAUUCAAUUGACCGGGUUUCUCGUCGGAAGCCAUAGAGGCCAACAGGAAAUGUAGGAGCAUUUUUCAAGUUCUGAAAUAAAAAGAAAUGCCAACCCAGAUUGCUAUAUCCAACAAAAUAUCCUUUAGGAAUGAAACAGAAGUAACGAUGAGGCAAUACAAAGAAUUGCCUGCAGACCUGGUUUAAAUAAAUGGUUACAGAAAACUCUUAAGGAAACCUGGAACAAAGGAAAAGCAAUAGAAGAGUAAAUACCUGAGUAAAUAGAUCAGAUCAUUCUACUCUUGAGUUCUUUAAAAUAUAUAUUAUUGUCAAAAGCAAAAAUUAUCACAUGGGGUUUCAACUGAUGUAUAUUUAAUACAUAAGACAACUACAACAUGAAGGUGAGGGGCAACGUGGCUGGACGGCGUGGAGGUUCCGUGCUCCAUUUCAGUGGCAAAAUACCAUUCCAGAAGGACUGGAAAAGCUAAGUCUGUAUAUUUUAAUUACUAAAGAAGUGUACAGCUGGGUGUGGUGGCUCACGCCUGUAAUCCCACCACUUUGGGAGAGUGAGGUGGGUGGAUCACUUGAGGUCAGGAGUUUGAGACCAGCUUGGCCAACAUGGUGAAACCCCAUCUCUACUAAGAAAUACAAAAAUUAGCUGUGUGUGGUUGGGGGCACCUGUAAUCUCAGCUUCUCAGGAGGCUGAGGCAGGAGAAUCACUUGAACCCAGGAGGUGGAGGUUGCAGUCAGUCGAGAUUGUGCCACGGCACUCCAGCCUGGGUGACAGAGCAAGACUCUGUCUAAAAAAAAAAAGGACAAUGAGAUAUACUAAAAUGGUCCAAUAUGUUAAUUAAAACAUACUACUAAAAAAA